AGAACAGCCAUUGGUGAGUGGGGCAGGGCAGGAGGGAACUGAAGAGUGAGAAAGCAUUAUUUCAGCAAAAGGUCUUUCCUCCCUUGCUCUCUCCUCCAACCACUGGCUCAGCCUCUCCGCCCGCUGCCUGUGAAUGAUGCAAUGGAAGGUGUGCUGGGGUCGCCCUGUGUCCCGUGCAUAGGAGCAUCUCAGCCUCCAGGUCCUCUCCUUUGGGGCUCACGGCACCCCCAUGCUACGAACCGCAGGCAGGGACGGCCUCUGUCGCCUGUCCACCUACUUGGAAGAACUCGAGGCUGUGGAACUGAAGAAGUUCAAGUUAUACCUGGGGACCGCGACAGAGCUGGGAGAAGGCAAGAUCCCCUGGGGAAGCAUGGAGAAGGCCGGUCCCCUGGAAAUGGCCCAGCUGCUCAUCACCCACUUCGGGCCAGAGGAGGCCUGGAGGUUGGCUCUCAGCACCUUUGAGCGGAUAAACAGGAAGGACCUGUGGGAGAGAGGACAGAGAGAGGACCUGGUGAGGGCAUUGACAAUGCAUAACCAUUUGCCGAGCGUUCUUCCCCGGACUGCAUCCGUUUAGUCUACUGAGAGGCAGCUCAGCGUUCCCAAGGAGACAGAUGUCUAGCUUUGCUCUUUCUGUCUGUGUGAUGCUGGAGAAUCGAUAUGCCCCUGGGCCUCCAUCUCCAUCUGUAAAACAAGGGCAUCAGGCAAGAUCGGCAGUUCUCAUGUUACUAUACCCCACCUGGUGGCCCGUCCUCACUUGGGAACCAGUCAACAUGCCUUCUGGAAGUCUCUCUUGUCACUCCAAGAAAAGAUCCCCAGGAAACCUACAGGGACUAUGUCCGCAGGAAAUUCCGGCUCAUGGAAGACCGCAAUGCGCGCCUAGGGGAAUGUGUCAACCUCAGCCACCGGUACACCCGGCUCCUGCUGGUGAAGGAGCACUCAAACCCCAUGCAGGUCCAGCAGCAGCUUCUGGACACAGGCCGGGGACACGCGAGGACCGUGGGACACCAGGCUAGCCCCAUCAAGAUAGAGACCCUCUUUGAGCCAGACGAGGAGCGCCCCGAGCCACCGCGCACCGUGGUCAUGCAAGGCGCGGCAGGGAUAGGCAAGUCCAUGCUGGCACACAAGGUGAUGCUGGACUGGGCGGACGGGAAGCUCUUCCAAGGCAGAUUUGAUUAUCUCUUCUACAUCAACUGCAGGGAGAUGAACCAGAGUGCCACGGAAUGCAGCAUGCAAGACCUCAUCUUCAGCUGCUGGCCUGAGCCCAGCGCGCCUCUCCAGGAGCUCAUCCGAGUUCCCGAGCGCCUCCUUUUCAUCAUCGACGGCUUCGAUGAGCUCAAGCCUUCUUUCCACGAUCCUCAGGGACCCUGGUGCCUCUGCUGGGAGGAGAAACGGCCCACGGAGCUGCUUCUUAACAGCUUAAUUCGGAAGAAGCUGCUCCCUGAGCUAUCUUUGCUCAUCACCACACGGCCCACGGCUUUGGAGAAGCUCCACCGUCUGCUGGAGCACCCCAGGCAUGUGGAGAUCCUGGGCUUCUCUGAGGCAGAAAGGAAGGAAUACUUCUACAAGUAUUUCCACAAUGCAGAGCAGGCGGGCCAAGUCUUCAAUUACGUGAGGGACAACGAGCCUCUCUUCACCAUGUGCUUCGUCCCCCUGGUGUGCUGGGUGGUGUGUACCUGCCUCCAGCAGCAGCUGGAGGGUGGGGGGCUGUUGAGACAGACGUCCAGGACCACCACUGCAGUGUACAUGCUCUACCUGCUGAGUCUGAUGCAACCCAAGCCGGGGGCCCCGCGCCUCCAGCCCCCACCCAACCAGAGAGGGUUGUGCUCCUUGGCGGCAGAUGGGCUCUGGAAUCAGAAAAUCCUAUUUGAGGAGCAGGACCUCCGGAAGCACGGCCUAGACGGGGAAGACGUCUCUGCCUUCCUCAACAUGAACAUCUUCCAGAAGGACAUCAACUGUGAGAGGUACUACAGCUUCAUCCACUUGAGUUUCCAGGAAUUCUUUGCAGCUAUGUACUAUAUCCUGGACGAGGGGGAGGGCGGGGCAGGCCCAGACCAGGACGUGACCAGGCUGUUGACCGAGUACGCGUUUUCUGAAAGGAGCUUCCUGGCACUCACCAGCCGCUUCCUGUUUGGACUCCUGAACGAGGAGACCAGGAGCCACCUGGAGAAGAGUCUCUGCUGGAAGGUCUCGCCGCACAUCAAGAUGGACCUGUUGCAGUGGAUCCAAAGCAAAGCUCAGAGCGACGGCUCCACCCUGCAGCAGGGCUCCUUGGAGUUCUUCAGCUGCUUGUACGAGAUCCAGGAGGAGGAGUUUAUCCAGCAGGCCCUGAGCCACUUCCAGGUGAUCGUGGUCAGCAACAUUGCCUCCAAGAUGGAGCACAUGGUCUCCUCGUUCUGUCUGAAGCGCUGCAGGAGCGCCCAGGUGCUGCACUUGUAUGGCGCCACCUACAGCGCGGACGGGGAAGACCGCGCGAGGUGCUCCGCAGGAGCGCACACGCUGUUGGUGCAGCUCAGACCAGAGAGGACCGUUCUGCUGGACGCCUACAGUGAACAUCUGGCAGCGGCCCUGUGCACCAAUCCAAACCUGAUAGAGCUGUCUCUGUACCGAAAUGCCCUGGGCAGCCGGGGGGUGAAGCUGCUCUGUCAAGGACUCAGACACCCCAACUGCAAACUUCAGAACCUGAGGCUGAAGAGGUGCCGCAUCUCCAGCUCAGCCUGCGAGGACCUCUCUGCAGCUCUCAUAGCCAAUAAGAAUUUGACAAGGAUGGAUCUCAGUGGCAACGGCGUUGGAUUCCCAGGCAUGAUGCUGCUUUGCGAGGGCCUGCGGCAUCCCCAGUGCAGGCUGCAGAUGAUUCAGUUGAGGAAGUGUCAGCUGGAGUCCGGGGCUUGUCAGGAGAUGGCUUCUGUGCUCGGCACCAACCCACAUCUGGUUGAGUUGGACCUGACAGGAAAUGCACUGGAGGAUUUGGGCCUGAGGUUACUAUGCCAGGGACUGAGGCACCCAGUCUGCAGACUACGGACUUUGUGGCUGAAGAUCUGCCGCCUCACUGCUGCUGCCUGUGACGAGCUGGCCUCAACUCUCAGUGUGAACCAGAGCCUGAGAGAGCUGGACCUGAGCCUGAAUGAGCUGGGGGACCUCGGGGUGCUGCUGCUGUGUGAGGGCCUCAGGCAUCCCACGUGCAAGCUCCAGACCCUGCGGUUGGGCAUCUGCCGGCUGGGCUCUGCCGCCUGUGAGGGUCUUUCUGUGGUGCUCCAGGCCAACCACAACCUCCGGGAGCUGGACUUGAGUUUCAACGACCUGGGAGACUGGGGCCUGUGGUUGCUGGCUGAGGGGCUGCAACAUCCCGCCUGCAGACUCCAGAAACUGUGGCUGGAUAGCUGUGGCCUCACAGCCAAGGCUUGUGAGAAUCUUUACUUCACCCUGGGGAUCAACCAGACCUUGACCGACCUUUACCUGACCAACAACGCCCUAGGGGACACAGGUGUCCGACUGCUUUGCAAGCGGCUGAGCCAUCCUGGCUGCAAACUCCGAGUCCUCUGGUUAUUUGGGAUGGACCUGAAUAAAAUGACCCACAGUAGGUUGGCAGCGCUUCGAGUAACAAAACCUUAUUUGGACAUUGGCUGCUGAAUGGUCCUAUCUGCUGGCUCUCCCCUGAGAUCUGGACAGAGGAAGAUGGGAGGGUGCUCAUCACCCCCCCAGCAUAAUGAUCAGCCUCCUUCCUAGAGACAGACUCAUGCAGAUUGAGAUCAAAAGUCCCUCUGCUUGGGAUCAAAUUAAUGUUUGACAGAGCUGGCCAGGCGUGGUGGCUCAUGUAUGUAAUCCUAGCACUUCGAGAGGCCGAGGCAGGUGGAUCACGAGGUCAGGAGUUUGAGAUUAGCCUGGCCAAGAUGGUGAAACCCUGUCUCUACUAAAAAUAAAAAAAAAUUAGCCAGGCAUGGUGGCGGGCACCUGUAGUCCCAGCUACUCAGGAGGCUGAGGCAGGAGAAUCGCUUGAACCCGGGAGGUGGAGGUUGCAGUGAGCCGAGAUCGCGCCACUGCACUCCAGCCUGGGCGACAGAGUGGGACUCCAUCUCAAAAAAAAAAAAAAAAAAA